AGGGAGAUUCGGCUGAUUCUUUUUUCAUUGUAGAAUCUGGAGAAGUGAAAAUUACUAUGAAAAGAAAGGGUAAAUCAGAAGUGGAAGAGAAUGGUGCAGUAGAAAUCGCUCGAUGCUCGCGGGGACAGUACUUUGGAGAGCUUGCCCUGGUAACUAACAAACCUCGAGCAGCUUCUGCCCACGCCAUUGGGACUGUCAAAUGUUUAGCAAUGGAUGUGCAAGCAUUUGAAAGGCUUCUGGGACCUUGCAUGGAAAUUAUGAAAAGGAACAUCGCUACCUAUGAAGAACAGUUAGUUGCCCUGUUUGGAACGAACAUGGAUAUUGUUGAACCCACUGCAUGAAGCAAAAGUAUGGAGCAAGACCUGUAGUGACAAAAUUACACAGUAGUGGUUAGUCCACUGAGAAUGUGUUUGUGUAGAUGCCAAGCAUUUUCUGUGAUUUCAGGUUUUUUCCUUUUUUUACAUUUACAACGUAUCAAUAAACAGUAGUGAUUUAAUAGUCAAUAGGCUUUAACAUCACUUUCUAAAGAGUAGUUCAUAAAAAAAUCAACAUACUGAUAAAAUGACUUUGUACUCCACAAAAUUAUGACUGAAAGGUUUAUUAAAAUGAUUGUAAUAUAUAGAAAGUAUCUGUGUUUAAGAAGAUAAUUAAAGGAUGUUAUCAUAGGCUAUAUGUGUUUUACUUAUUCAGACUGAUAAUCAUAUUAGUGACUAUCCCCAUGUAAGAGGGCACUUGGCAAUUAAACAUGCUACACAGCAUGGCAUCACUUUUUUUUAUAACUCAUUAAACACAGUAAAAUUUUAAUCAUUUUUGUUUUAAAGUUUUCUAGCUUGAUAAGUUAUGUGCUGGCCUUGGCCUAUUGGUGAAAUGGUAUAAAAUAUCAUAUGCAGUUUUAAAACUUUUUAUAUUUUUGCAAUAAAGUACAUUUUGACUUUGUUGGCAUAAUGUCAGUAACAUACAUAUUCCAGUGGUUUUAUGGACAGGCAAUUUAGUCAUUAUGAUAAUAAGGAAAACAGUGUUUUAGAUGAGAGAUCAUUAAUGCAUUUUUCCCUCAUCAAGCAUAUAUCUGCUUUUUUUUAUUUUGCAAUUCUCUGUAUUCUAUGUCUUUAAAAAUUUGAUCUUGACAUUUAAUGUCACAAAGUUUUGUUUUUUUAAAAAGUGAUUUAAACUUAAGAUCCGACAUUUUUUGUAUUCUUUAAGAUUUUACACCUAAAAAAUCUCUCCUAUCCCAAAAAUAAUGUGGGAUCCUUAUCAGCAUGCCCACAGUUUAUUUCUUUGUUCUUCACUAGGCCUGCAUAAUACAGUCCUAUGUAGACAUCUGUUCCCUUGGGUUUCCGUUCUUUCUUAGGAUGGUUGCCAACCCACAAUCUCAUUGAUCAGCAGCCAAUAUGGGUUUGUUUGGUUUUUUUAAUUCUUAAAAACAUCCUCUAGAGGAAUAGAAACAAAUUUUUAUGAGCAUAACCCUAUAUAAAGACAAAAUGAAUUUCUGACCUUACCAUAUAUACCAUUAGGCCUUGCCAUUGCUUUAAUGUAGACUCAUAGUUGAAAUUAGUGCAGAAAGAACUCAGAUGUACUAGAUUUUCAUUGUUCAUUGAUAUGCUCAGUAUGCUGCCACAUAAGAUGAAUUUAAUUAUAUUCAACCAAAGCAAUAUACUCUUACAUGAUUUCUAGGCCCCAUGACCCAGUGUCUAGAGACAUUAAUUCUAACCAGUUGUUUGCUUUUAAAUGAGUGAUUUCAUUUUGGGAAACAGGUUUCAAAUGAAUAUAUAUACAUGGGUAAAAUUACUCUGUGCUAGUGUAGUCUUACUAGAGAAUGUUUAUGGUCCCACUUGUAUAUGAAAAUGUGGUUAGAAUGUUAAUUGGAUAAUGUAUAUAUAAGAAGUUAAAGUAUGUAAAGUAUAACUUCAGCCACAUUUUUAGAACACUGUUUAACAUUUUUGCAAAACCUUCUUGUAGGAAAAGAGAGCUCUCUACAUGAAGAUGACUUGUUUUAUAUUUCAGAUUUUAUUUUAAAAGCCAUGUCUGUUAAACAAGAAAAAACACAAAAGAACUCCAGAUUCCUGGUUCAUCAUUCUGUAUUCUUACUCACUUUUUCAAGUUAUCUAUUUUGUUGCAUAAACUAAUUGUUAACUAUUCAUGGAACAGCAAACGCCUGUUUAAUAAAGAACUUUGACCAAGGCUAUAAAUGCCACGUACAUUAUUUUCAGUAUUGUUGGUUAUAUUUAAAUUUUCCUUACAAUAAAGCACACUUUUAUAAUAAAAUACAUGAAUUAUUGUUUUUCAUACUUUUUUGCUUGUUUCUUUAAAGUUUUCUGACGUGCAUAAUGCAUAAUUCAUUGAAAAGCAUGAUAGCAAUGUGGCAUGUGGAAGCGAACCCCCAGGGCAUAACAUAGUAAGAAAGUAUGGUUCUGUAUGGCAAUAGGUUUUUAAAAUUAUUAGCUAUUCAUCAUGUGUGGGAGAAAUAAUUGUGGUGUGUUGCAGAUUUAUUUGGCCAUUUAGAAUAACCAAAUCAAUCUGGCUAACUAGGAAUUUAUGUGUAAAAUUAUCUGAUUAAAACAGCUCAAGUUUGA